AGUCGAGGGUCGGACUGGUCAGGGUUCAGGCGGGAUCCGGCGUCCGAGUCCUGGUGGGCCGGCCUGGGGCAGGAUCUGGCUCUGGCUGCGGGUCCUGACUCGGGUCAGGGUUGGGCCUCCGAUCCAGCCCGCUCCGGGGCAGGGUUCAAUCCCGCAUUUGCCGAAGUCCCUGGGGCUGGCCGGGGUGGAAGACGGGGAGGGCUCUAUGUCUGGGAAGGGGCUCUGAAGACCACGUGGGGGCGCUCGAAGGGGCCUGGGGCCACCCUCCUCUCUGGGUCAAAGGUCAUCGCACCGGCAGGGGAGAACUUCCUCCUCCUUGGCUCUCCCCACUUACUUCCUGAUAACCUGGUAGAGGUCUCCCGCGGGCGGGGAGGGGGAGGCGUAGCAACUUUAGGCAACUUCCCAAAGGUGUGCGCAGGUUGGGGGCGGGACGCGGCGCCCCGGGAGGUGGCGGCCUCUGCGACAGCGGGAGUAUAAGAGUGGACCUGCAGGCUGGUCGCGAGGAGGUGGAGCGGCGCCCGCCGUGUGCCUGGGACCGGCAUGCUGGGGCAGGAGGGCAGCCGCGUGUCAGGUGUGAAAAGCUCUGGAGGUGUUUUCAUGAGUCCGUGCCUGUGCGUGUGGAUGUGGGGAGACCUAGUGAGAGUGUGUGUGAUCAUGAGCCUUGACUGAGUUCGUGGAUGGGGUGUGCGCUCCAGGAGAAGUGUGUGAGCACAAGUGUGAGCAGGAGUGAGCACGGGUUUGGGAAGGCCGGUGCAAGUGUGAAAGCCCUCAGCAGAGAGCGAGCCUGCGUGGGCUUGUGGGGCUCCUGAGCACCCCGGUGAGUGGAGUGUGUGAACUCGGUGUGAGCACGUCCACUGGCCUUGGGUCUGCUCUCCAAUGCAGAAUACCCAGAUGAGGGCAGGGUCUCAGAGGUCCCCCCAACAUCUGGAGAAAACUGGGAAGUAUCCUGCUCCUGGCUAGGGAUUCCAGGUGGGGUUGAAGGUUGCCUGGGGGCUACGGUUACCCUGCUCCCUGGCCUGGGUGGGAGUAGGGGCUUUCUAAGCCUCCCCCAGGUUCCCAAGGGGGAGACCUGCUGUCAGUUACUGGCCCUGAAGACUCUGUUUCCAUGGCAACAGCUAGGAGGGGGCAGUGUUCCUGGGCAGUCCUUCCUUGGACUCUGCCCCCCUUCUUCCCCACUUGCUGGGCUUGGAAGCCUGGCCCUAGGCCCGAGGUUGGGCAACCCGUGUGGCAGGGUGUCUCCCAUCCCCCAUACCAGUGCUUUCCUGCGAACCUAUGGGUCUCUCCGUGCAGGUGACCAGCGCCAUGUCCAGCCAGGUGGUGGGCAUUGAGCCUCUCUACAUCAAGGCAGAGCCGGCCAGCCCUGACAGUCCAAAGGGUUCCUCGGAGACAGAGACCGAGCCUCCUGUGGCCCUGGCCCCUGGUCCAGCUCCCACUCGCUGCCUCCCAGGCCACAAGGAAGAGGAGGAUGGGGAGGGGGCUGGGCCUGGCGAGCAGGGCGGUGGGAAGCUGGUGCUCAGCUCCCUGCCCAAGCGCCUCUGCCUGGUCUGUGGGGACGUGGCCUCCGGCUACCACUAUGGUGUGGCAUCCUGUGAGGCCUGCAAAGCCUUCUUCAAGAGGACCAUCCAGGACCUGUGCUUGCCCGGGGAGAGUCAGGGCUCUCCUGUCAGCUGGGUCCCCUCCCAGCCCCGGGAGGCCGCCACUGGAGCCCUGCCUCUUCCUGGCAGGGAGCAUCGAGUACAGCUGUCCGGCCUCCAACGAGUGUGAGAUCACCAAGCGGAGACGCAAGGCCUGCCAGGCCUGCCGCUUCACCAAGUGCCUGCGGGUGGGCAUGCUCAAGGAGGGAGUGCGCCUGGACCGCGUCCGGGGUGGGCGGCAGAAGUACAAGCGGCGGCCGGAGGUGGACCCACUGCCCUUCCCGGGCCCCUUCCCUGCUGGGCCCCUGGCAGUCGCUGGAGGCCCCCGGAAGACAGCAGCCCCAGUGAAUGCACUGGUGUCUCAUCUGCUGGUGGUUGAGCCUGAGAAGCUCUAUGCCAUGCCUGACCCCGCAGGCCCUGAUGGGCACCUCCCAGCCGUGGCUACCCUCUGUGACCUCUUUGACCGAGAGAUUGUGGUCACCAUCAGCUGGGCCAAGAGCAUCCCAGGCUUCUCAUCGCUGUCGCUGUCUGACCAGAUGUCAGUACUGCAGAGCGUGUGGAUGGAGGUGCUGGUGCUGGGUGUGGCCCAGCGCUCACUGCCACUGCAGGAUGAGCUGGCCUUCGCUGAGGACUUAGUCCUGGAUGAAGAGGGGGCACGGGCAGCUGGCCUGGGGGAACUGGGGGCUGCCCUGCUGCAACUAGUGCGGCGGCUGCAGGCCCUGCGGCUGGAGCGAGAGGAGUAUGUUCUACUAAAGGCCUUGGCCCUUGCCAAUUCAGACUCUGUGCACAUCGAAGAUGCCGAGGCUGUGGAGCAGCUGCGAGAAGCUCUGCACGAGGCCCUGCUGGAGUAUGAAGCCGGCCGGGCUGGCCCCGGAGGGGGUGCUGAGCGGCGGCGGGCGGGCAGGCUGCUGCUCACGCUACCGCUCCUCCGCCAGACAGCGGGCAAAGUGCUGGCCCAUUUCUAUGGGGUGAAGCUGGAGGGCAAGGUGCCCAUGCACAAGCUGUUCUUGGAGAUGCUCGAGGCCAUGAUGGACUGAGGCAAGGGGUGGGACUGGUGGGGGUUCUGGCAGGACCUGCCUAGCAUGGGGUCAGCCCCAAGGGCUGGGGCGGAGCUGGGGUCUGGGCAGUGCCACAGCCUGCUGGCAGGGCCAGGGCAAUGCCAUCAGCCCCUGGGAACAGGCCCCACGCCCUCUCCUCCCCCUCCUAGGGGGUGUCAGAAGCUGGGAACGUGUGUCCAGGCUCUGGGCACAGUGCUGCCCCUUGCAAGCCAUAACGUGCCCCCAGAGUGUAGGGGGCCUUGCGGAAGCCAUAGGGGGCUGCACGGGAUGCGUGGGAGGCAGAAACCUAUCUCAGGGAGGGAAGGGGAUGGAGGCCAGAGUCUCCCAGUGGGUGAUGCUUUUGCUGCUGCUUAAUCCUACCCCCUCUUCAAAGCAGAGUGGGACUUGGAGAGCAAAGGCCCAUGCCCCCUUCGCUCCUCCUCUCAUCAUUUGCAUUGGGCAUUAGUGUCCCCCCUUGAAGCAAUAACUCCAAGCAGACUCCAGCCCCUGGACCCCUGGGGUGGCCAGGGCUUCCCCAUCAGCUCCCAACGAGCCUCCUCAGGGGGUAGGAGAGCACUGCCUCUAUGCCCUGCAGAGCAAUAACACUAUAUUUAUUUUUGGGUUUGGCCAGGGAGGCGCAGGGACAUGGGGCAAGCCAGGGCCCAGAGCCCUUGGCUGUACAGAGACUCUAUUUUAAUGUAUAUUUGCUGCAAAGAGAAACCGCUUUUGGUUUUAAACCUUUAAUGAGAAAAAAAUAUAUAAUACCGAGCUCAAAAA